ACUCAGCGGUUUUCCCUCCCCCAACGGCGCGCCGGCUGUGGCCGGCGCAGAGUAGUGCUCGGGCCGGGGGUCGCCUCCCGCCUCCCGCCUCCCGCCUCCCGCCGCCCGCCGCCCGCGUCGCCCUCGCCGCCGUUGGGCCGCGCCGCGCCGCCAUGUCGGGCCCCGGACCGCGGGAGCCGCCGCCGGAGGCAGGCGCGGCAGGCGGCGAGGCGGCCGUCGAGGGCGCGGGCGGCGGGGACGCGGCGCUGGGCGAGCCGGGGCUGAGCUUCACGACCACCGACCUGAGCCUGGUGGAGAUGACGGAGGUGGAGUACACGCAGCUGCAGCACAUCCUCUGCUCGCACAUGGAGGCGGCGGCUGACGGCGAGCUCGAGACGCGCCUCAACUCGGCGCUGCUGGCGGCGGCGGGCCCGGGCGCAGGCGCGGGCGGCUUCGCGGCGGGCGGUCAGGGGGGCGCGGCGCCCGUGUACCCCGUGCUGUGCCCGUCCGCGCUGGCGGCCGACGCGCCCUGCCUGGGCCACAUCGACUUCCAGGAGCUGCGCAUGAUGCUGCUAAGCGAGGCGGGCGCGGCGGAGAAGACGUCGGGCGGCGGGGACGGAGCGAGGGCCCGGGCCGACGGCGCCGCCAAGGAGGGCGCGGGCGCGGCUGCGGCUGCGGCUGGACCCGACGGCGCGCCCGAGGCCCGGGCCAAGCCGGCCGUGCGCGUCCGCCUGGAGGACCGCUUCAACAGCAUCCCCGCCGAGCCGCCGCCCGCGCCGCGCGGCCCCGAGCCCCCCGAGCCGGGCGGGGCGCUCAACAAUUUGGUAACUCUCAUUCGACAUCCAUCUGAACUAAUGAAUGUUCCUCUUCAGCAACAAAACAAAUGUACAGCAUUAGUGAAAAAUAAAACUGCGGCUACAACUACUGCUUUGCAAUUUACAUACCCACUGUUUACUACAAAUGCUUGCUCUACUAGUGGAAAUUCUAAUCUUUCACAGACACAGAGUUCUAGUAACUCAUGUUCUGUACUUGAAGCUGCCAAGCACCAGGAUAUUGGAUUGCCUAGAGCAUUUUCUUUCUGUUAUCAGCAAGAAAUUGAAUCCACUAAACAGACGUUAGGUAGUAGAAACAAAGUUUUGCCUGAGCAAGUUUGGAUUAAAGUGGGAGAAGCAGCGCUAUGCAAACAAGCACUGAAGAGGAAUCGGAGUAGAAUGCGUCAGUUGGACACAAAUGUAGAGCGAAGAGCCCUUGGAGAGAUUCAGAAUGUGGGCGAAGGUGCCACCGCCACACAAGGCGCUUGGCAGUCCUCGGAGUCCUCACAGGCAAACCUGGGGGAGCAGGCCCAGAGUGGGCCCCAGGGAGGAAGGUCUCAACGUAGGGAGAGGCAUAACCGAAUGGAAAGAGAUAGAAGGCGCAGAAUCCGCAUUUGCUGUGAUGAGUUGAAUCUCUUAGUGCCGUUCUGCAAUGCCGAGACUGACAAGGCCACAACUCUGCAGUGGACCACAGCAUUCCUGAAAUACAUCCAGGAAAGACAUGGAGAUUCUCUUAAAAAGACUGGGUGACUAUACUUCCAUGGACUGGGUGAACAUACUUUUGUGGACUGGUUGACUAUACCUUUGUGGACUCGGUGAAUAUACUUCUGCGGACCGGGUGACCGUGCUUCUGUGGAAUGGGUGAAUAUACUUCUGCGGACCAGGUGACUAUGCUUCUGUCAACCAGGUGAAUAUACUUCUGUGGACCGGGUGACUGUACUUCUGUGGACCGGGUGAAUAUACUUCUGUGGACCGGGUGAAUAUACUUCUGUGGACUGGGUGACUAGGGAGGAGCCGGCGUGUUAGCGCCAGCAUAUGCAGUCCCUCAGGACAGCCAGCCUGCCGUGAUCCUGUCUGUGUGGUCGUGGCAGUGGCCUGCAGCAAGCCAUCGUGGUUGGCUGGAACUAGACGUGUGAUUUGAAUGCAGGAGUUCAGUCAGCCCCUCAGUGGCCUAAAAGGAAGAAGGUGUCAGUCACAGGGCUGGUUCUGGGCCCUGCCUUGGGGGGACCCCAGUUCCAGGGUUCUGGGCCCUGCCUUCAGGGGACCCGAGUUCCAGGGUCCUGGGCCCUGCCUUUGGGGGACCCGAGUUCCAGGUCCCGGCCUCAGCGUUGCAGUGGCCAGGGUCAGUGGCUCUUUGGCCCUCUAGGAGUGAGCAGACCUUAGUGAAAUAGAUCCACAGGGUCCUGACUUUGUACCUGGUCCAAGCUGUUGGGGAAUUGCUGCUGUUGACCCAGGCAGGAGUCUGACUAGAGAACAAACUAAGGUUGCUGCAACAAACAAGGACCUCUUCCAAGAAGGGCUCCCAGGCCUGGCGCAGUGACUCAUGCCUGUGAUCCCAGCACUUGGGAGGCCGAGGCGGGUGGAUCAUUUGAGGCCAGGAGUUCGAGACCAGCUUGGCCAACAUGAUGAGACCCCCGUCUCUAUUAAAAAUACAAAAAUUAGCCAGGCGUGGUGGCGCCUGUAGUCCCAGCUACUCAGGAGGUUGAAGCAGGAGAAUUGUUGAACCCGGGAGGCGGAGGUUGCAAUGAGCCAAGAUAGCACCACUGCACUGCAGCCUGGGUGACAGAGCGAGACUCCAUCUCAAAAGAAGGGCUCCUGUGUCUACGUCAUGGUGGGGCUAGAGAGAGGUCCCCGCAGCUGGGCUGUGUUGAGUGAGGGCUCGUCUCUUCAGCGCCAGGCAAUAGUUUGUCUUGUCUCUGUCCCUUUUCUGUGUCCACAUGACAUUUACAUCUUGCGAGUUGCAUAAUUUAAGUUGUUUAUUUACAUUAUACAUUUAAUUGCAUUCUAUAGCGAUGCUAUGUUGAAUGUAUUCUGAUCGGAUCGUUUAUGGUUAUUUACAAUGCAGUUACUCUUGAAGAUUAUUGUUAGAGGUAGACUGUUGAUUUGUUUUGAUAAAAUAAAGCUUUUGUGUUUUAAAAAA